CCGCCCACAAAGCGCUGAUUUCCGCCGAGGAUCGCUGAACCCCUAAGCCCUUGACCUCUUUGAAGGGGUGUUGAGCCCUCUUUGGGGGCCCUGGGCCUCUCCUACCCUAAACUCUUCUCCACGGGCUCGCCGGGCCUCCCCUCUCCCCCGAGGCUUCCCACUCGGGGUGGCCCCUUGCUCCGGGUGUGCAGGUGAACCCCCACUUCUCUGACCCCCAAAUAGGAGCUUGUCUCCGGACAGUAGCACAGUUCCCGGCACAGAGGAGACCUCGGCUAACAGGUGUUGGAUGAAUGGAUGUACAGACCCUGUGCUUUCCCCACGCCCCCCAACUUAGGACGCAGCCCUGCCUCCCGGGUGUGUGCUCGAUGGCCCUGCAGCCCUCCUCAGUGGGGCACGCAGGUGGGGCGCGCAAGAGGAGUCACAGGCCGGCAAUGUUGGGAAGACUCCUAGGAUCCGAUUGAUAGACACCAACCGGGUGCUGCAGGUUGUGAAAUGGCCCCUUCCUGCCCAGAGCUGCCCAAUGAGGUUCUCAUGGGAAAAUGCAUUCAGACUCCCCGGAACAGUUGACUUGGAGCCUCUGUCUUUGCUCUCUCUGCCUUGAGCCCUGGAACCUCUCCUCCUUUCGUCCCUUCAUUCCUAAAACACUGGAGAUUUUGAUUCGCUUUCCAAGGACAAUGUCUUCGAGAAUAACCGUUUGGCCUUUGAAGUGGCUGAGAAGGAGCUGGGGAUCCCCGCUCUCCUGGACCCCAAUGACAUGGUCUCCAUGAGCGUCCCUGACUGCCUCAGCAUCAUGACCUAUGUGUCCCAGUAUUACAACCACUUCUGCAGUCCUGGCCAAGCUGGUGUCUCGCCACCCAGAAAGGGCCUUGCACCCUGUUCCCCGCCGUCUGUAGCACCCACUCCAGUGGAACCAGAAGAUGUGGCUCAGGGCGAGGAGCUCUCCUCAGGCAGCCUGUCAGAGCAGGGCACCGGCCAGACCCCCAGCAGCACGUGCGCAGCCUGCCAGCAGCAUGUGCACUUGGUGCAGCGCUACCUGGCUGACGGCAGGCUGUACCAUCGCCACUGCUUCCGGUGUCGGCGGUGCUCCAGCACCCUGCUCCCUGGGGCUUAUGAGAAUGGGCCUGAGGAGGGCACCUUUGUGUGUGCAGAACACUGUGCCAGGCUGGGCCCGGGGACACGGUCGGGGACCAGGCCUGGGCCCUUCUCACAGCCAAAGCAGCAGCACCAGCAGCAACUCGCAGAAGAUGCCAAGGAUGUUCCAGGAGGCGGCCCCAGCUCCAGUGCUCCUGCAGGGGCUGAGGCCGAUGGACCCAAGGCCAGCCCUGAGGCCCGGCCGCAGAUCCCUACCAAGCCCCGGGUUCCUGGCAAACUACAGGAGCUGGCCAGCCCCCCUGCGGGCCGCCCCACCCCUGCCCCCAGGAAGGCCUCUGAGAGCACCACCCCAGCACCCCCCACGCCCCGGCCCCGCUCCAGUCUGCAGCAGGAGAACCUGGUGGAGCAGGCUGGCAGCAGCAGCCUGGUGAACGGGAGACUGCACGAACUGCCUGUCCCCAAGCCGAGGGGGACACCGAAGCCGUCCGAGGGGACACCAGCCCCCAGGAAGGACCCCCCAUGGAUCACGCUGGUGCAGGCAGAACCAAAGAAGAAGCCAGCCCCACUUCCCCCAAGCAGCAGCCCGGGGCCACCAAGCCAGGACAGCAGGCAGGUGGAGAAUGGAGGCACCGAGGAGGUGGCCCAGCCGAGCCCAACGGCCAGCCUGGAGUCCAAACCCUAUAACCCCUUUGAGGAGGAGGAGGAGGACAAGGAGGAAGAGGCUCCAGCUGCACCCAGCCUGGCCACCAGCCCUGCCCUGGGCCACCCGGAGUCCACACCCAAGUCCCUGCACCCCUGGUACGGCAUCACCCCUACCAGCAGCCCCAAGACAAAGAAGCGCCCUGCCCCGCGCGCACCCAGCGCGUCCCCACUGGAUAAUGUGUUUGGAAGCAUCAUAUCCAUCAGCCACGAGGAGAUAAAUUGGUGCCCGGCAGUGCCUGUCCCAGAGCUGGUGGCUGCGAGGGCUGCGUGCUCCUCCCCUCUGCCUCCGCACUGCAGAUCAGGGGCAGAGGAGGGGCCACCUCUCUUCCUCUGGCAUUCCCAAGCUCUCCACGCCUCCCGCCUCUCGCACUCGGAGCCGCCCUCGGCCACACCAUCGCCAGCGCUCAGCGUGGAGAGCCUGUCGUCUGAGAGCGCCAGCCAGACUGCAGGUGCAGAGCUUCUGGAGCCGCCAGCUGUGCCCAAGAGCUCCUCAGAGCCUGCUGUCCAUGCCCCUGGUACCCCUGGAAACCCUGUCAGCCUCUCUACCAACUCCUCCCUGGCCUCCUCUGGGGAACUAGUGGAGCCUAGAGUGGAACAAAUGCCUCAAGCCAGCCCUGGCCUUGCCCCCAGGACCAGGGGCAGCUCAGGUCCCCAGCCAGCCAAGCCCUGCAGUGGCGCCACCCCAACGCCUCUCUUGUUGGUUGGAGACAGGAGCCCGGUGCCUUCCCCUGGAAGCUCGUCCCCACAGCUGCAGGUAAAGUCCUCCUGCAAGGAGAAUCCUUUUAACCGGAAGCCAUCACCUGCAGCGUCCCCAGCCACAAAGAAGGCCACCAAGGGAUCCAAGCCAGUGAGGCCACCUGCCCCUGGACACGGCUUUCCACUCAUCAAACGCAAGGUCCAGGCUGACCAGUACAUCCCUGAGGAGGACAUCCAUGGAGAGAUGGAUACCAUUGAGCGCCGGCUGGAUGCCCUGGAGCACCGUGGGGUGCUGCUGGAGGAGAAGCUGCGUGGCGGCCUGAAUGAGGGCCGUGAGGAUGACAUGCUGGUGGACUGGUUCAAGCUCAUCCACGAGAAGCACCUACUGGUGCGGCGAGAGUCCGAGCUCAUCUAUGUCUUCAAGCAGCAGAACCUGGAGCAGCGCCAGGCUGAUGUCGAGUAUGAGCUCCGGUGCCUCCUCAAUAAGCCAGAAAAGGACUGGACGGAGGAGGACCGGGCCCGGGAGAAGGUGCUGAUGCAGGAGCUUGUGACCCUCAUUGAGCAGCGCAACGCUAUCAUCAACUGCCUGGAUGAGGACCGGCAGAGGGAGGAAGAGGAAGACAAGAUGUUGGAAGCCAUGAUCAAGAAGAAAGGUGAGGCCCUUGCUGGGGAUGAGGCUGAGUUCCAGAGGGAGGCUGAACCUGAGGGCAAGAAGAAGGGGAAGUUCAAGACCAUGAAGAUGUUGAAACUGCUAGGAAACAAACGUGAUGCCAAGAGCAAGUCCCCCAGAGACAAGAGCUAACAGCACGAGAAGCCAGUUGGGGACUGCCCCCUCCUGGAGCAGCUCCUGGGCUGUGCUCUGUUUGAAGGGGGCGCCCUGCUCCCCUCAGAUCAGUCAGGAGGAAGAUGACUAAGGGGAGGGAUCCUCUGGGUGAUGGCCUCUUCCUCCUCAGGGACCUCUGACUGCUCUGGGCCAAAGAAUCUCUUGUUUCUUCUCCGAGCCCCAGGCAGCGGUGAUUCAGCCCUGCCCAACCUGAUUCUGAUGACUGCGGAUGCUGUGACGGACCCAAGGGGCAAAUAGGGUCCCAGGGUCCAGGGAGGGGCGCCUGCUGAGCACUUCCGCCCCUCACCCUGCCCAGCCCCUGCCAUGAGCUCUGGGCUGGGUCUCCGCCUCCAGGGUUCUGCUCUUCCAGGCAGGCCAGCAAGUGGCGCUGGGCCACACUGGCUUCUUCCUGCCCCAUCCCUGGCUCUGAGUCUCUGUCUUCCUGUCCUGUGCAGGCGCCCUUGGAUCUCAGUUUCCCUCACUCAGGAACUCUGUUUCUGAAGUCUUCAGUUAAGUUUGAGUUUAUGACUGAGUGGCCUGUACUGUCAGACGUGAAUGGGCCUGACGGGCAAAUCCAUCCCUCUCUCCCUCACAGUUCCAGGAGCGGCUUCCCUCGUCUCCCCUUACUCCACAGGGAGCCUCCCUUGCCAGGACCAGGGCUGCGACGGCCAUGCUGGGGCAGGUGAGUGCUCUGUUAGCUGCUCCCAGUGCUGUCCCCAGGCUGCAGUUCUGGUCCCUGGUUGUCAGGUAGGAAGGGUGCACUUGAAGCAGGUGCUCAUCUCGGUUCCUUAACGUUUAUAGUCUGACCCCUCACUUAGGCUUUCCUCUGCCACCCCGGUCCAGGGAAGAGGCUCGCUCCCGCCCAUGGUCAUCACUGGUCUGUCUGCUCUGUUGUCUGUUCUUUCCCUGACUCCCUCCCACCGAAGGCCUGAUGGCUACUCACCCCUCUGGGAUGGCUAUGGGAGAGGAGGAGUGAUGGGGACCGCCACCUUUUCUGCAGGAAAUGUGCCCAGCAGCUCUUGGUCAAAGCACUGUUGCUAUAAGCUAUCUCUGGGAUGCCUCUAGGCCCCCUUCCCUCUACACACCUCUGGGAAAAGAUUACACUGUAUUAACUCUCGAGGAGUUUCCUCACCAAUAAACAGACAACCUCAACUGCCAGUGCCCUGCAGCCUCGGGCCACAGCGGCAGCCUUGUUUGCCUUCCCACCUGCCUCUGCCACACCUGGUGGCUGAACAUCUCUGGUCGCCCAGAGGCCAUGUUGGGGCCAUCCUCCAAGAGGGAUCUCUGCCCUCACCGCCUGCCACUGGGCAGGAUCCCUUUCCUCUGCAGGGAGAGGUGGCUCCUCGGCCAUGCAGCCCCUGGCAGGCUCCUUCUAAACAUGCCUGUUGACCUGGAGCUGGCGCCACCAACUCCAGGGCCUUUCCAGGGCCAGACAGGUAACACGCAUGAACCCGAGUGACAGCUCUGACGGGCUGUUUCGGUGUCAGGAGACAAAGCUGGCAGGGGCAGGGGUGAACUGGAGGCAAGUCAAGUCACCUGUGGCCUGUGGGGCUGAAUGUGGGCCCGGUGUUGCCAGAUCCUUUGUCAUAAGAAGCUAGAAAUCCAGAUUUUAUGUGUGUGUAAUUUGUAAAUGCUGAAAGCUAGCCUGAAUUUUUUUUUUUUUUUUUUGAGACAGAGUCUCGCUCUGUCGCCCAGGCUGGAGUGCAGUGGCGCGAUCUCAGCUCACUGCAAGCUCCGCCUCCUGGGUUCACGCCAUCCUCCUGCCUCGGCCUCCUGAGCAGCUGGGACUACAGGCGCAUGCUACGACGCCUGGCUAAUUUUUUGUAUUUUUAGUAGAGACGGGGUUUCACCGUGUUAACCAGGAUGGUCUCGAUCUCCUGACCUUGUGAUCCACCCACCUUGGCCUCCCAAAGUGCUGGGAUUACAGGCGUGAGCCACCACGCCCGGCCACUAGCCUGAAUUUCAAUCAAG